AAGGCUGUGGAACACAGCCCACAAGACAGAUAUCUGAGAAAACAGAAACAGAGUCUGCUGGGUUGGCAGCAACCUCCUUGAUACAACAGAGAGUCCUUGCCACUCUUGACCAACAGGGCUUGAUAUUUGCUGUGGACCAGUGACAGUUGGAUGUUUUUCACUCUGUCCCUUUCCAAAUGGAAGCUUAUUCUGCAGUUUUUCCUGCUUUUUAAUCAUUGCAUAUGAUUGUGUUGGGAACCAGUAACUUUUAUUUCAGUUUACAUGUCAUCUGACCCUAGGGAAACACAAGGAGACCUGAUGGAAAGGCAUGAACAAAGAUCCUGAACUUUGAGAAGAAAGUAAGAGAAUUAGAUAAACAGGAAGAAAAAUGUGACAUUGGUGCCAAAGAGGUGGAUUAUGAAAAUUCUCUUUACCAGCAUGAUACAACCGUACUCUAGUUCCUUUAUCUCUGCUUGCAAUAGCUGCUAUUCCUUAAUUUUUUUUUAAUAUUUGCCACUCUGGGAGGUACAAAGCAAUAUGACAAUGUUAAUUUAGUUUUCAUUUUUAUGACUUCUAGUGCAUUAGAGCCUCUUUUUAAUAUAUUUAUUGGCUAUUUGGAUUUGCUCUUUUGUGAACUGCAUAUUCAUAUCUUGUGUUUAUUUUUCCACCAAGUUGUUUGGGAUUUUUGGUCAACUUAUAAGAGUUCUGUGUAUAUUAAUUAUAGUUAUAAACCCUUACUAGGUCCAUCAUCUGCUUUGCAAAUAUUUGUUCCAAAUCUAAUAAUUGUCAGUUAGCACAUUGCUUACAGUUCCUUUUGCCAUACAAAAUUUUUAGUAUUAAAUUCUCAGAUAUAUUAAUCUUUAAAAAUAUCUUCCAGGAUUCUUUAAAUUCAGGUUUUUCUUUCCGCUAGAUAUUCUUCUAGAUUUUUUCUAAAAUUCUUAUUUUAAUUAUUAUAUUUAAGUCUUUUAACUGAAAUUGACUUUUGAAUAUGUGAGAUGUAGGAAUUCAAUUCUUUUUCUUAUAAAGGGACAGUCAGUUGUGUCAACACCAAUUAUUAAAUAAACAUUUUUUUCCCUAAAUUGAAAUAAUAAUGUCAACAUCUUAAAUUUUCAUCUUUCCUGUUGUGGAUGGACUAUUUGUCUACUCCUAUGCCAGUUCCACAUGCUGGAUUAUGGUGGUUUUAUGUUCUGAUAUCUGAGAAAUCCUCCUCAUUAUUCUGCUUCUAGAUACAUGUAUUUUUCUUGGCUAUUUGUGAGUAUAUUUUUCUUCCAGCUGAACUUUAAAGUCAUUGUAUAUAGUUCUAAUAAACAAAUCCAAGUUAGUAUUCUAAUUGGAAUUGCAAGAAAUAUAUUAAUUGAGUUGAGAUAAUUAGCUUUUUUUUUUAGACAGCGUCUCACUCUGUUACCUAGGCUCACUGCAACCUCAGCCUCCUGGGCUCAAGCAAUUCUCAUGUCUCAGCCUCCUGAGUGGCUGGGAUUAUAGGUGUGUGCCACCAUGCACAGCUAAUUUUCGUAUUUUUUGUAGAGACAGGGUUUCACCAUGUUGGCCAGGCUGGUCUUGAACUCCCAGGCAUAAGCAUUCUGCCUGUCUCAGCCUCCCAAAAAGCUGGGAUUACUAGCAUGAGCCACCAUGCCUGGCCUAUAAUUAGCUUUUUCAUAAUUAAAUCUUAUCCAAGAAUUUGGUGUGCCUUUCAAUUUGUUCACACCUUGAUUUUUAUAUUGAAAAUGUUAUAGUUUUGUUCAUGUCGAUCCUUUAUUUAUUUUGUUAAAAUUUUUGAUGAAUUGAUUGCAUUAAUGACAUCACAGGGAGACUACAUUUUUCCAUCUCAUGUAACUUGCUUUGGUCAAAAGAAUGCAGAAGUGACAGUAUGCUAUUUCUACUCCUAGGCUUUAAUAUGCCUUGUAUGUUUCUGCUUGUUCUAUUUUACCUUUCCCAUAGCCAUGAAAAUAGCUUCUCCCAUAGUUGCUGCCCCUUUAACCUGGAUACAGGCCCUGAAACACAGUCAUCUACCCAAGCCCAGCCAAGAAUUAUGGGUGAAAAUACCUCAUAUGAUGAUCCAUGCAAAGGUACCAUUUGCCGUUCCCACCGUGCUCUUAUGAGGAAAGCAGCUCCCUGUUUUAUCUGCAUGAAGUUGUUGUGACUUACGCCAUAUACAUAAACUAUAACAAACCCUGCCAUUUUGAUCACAGCAGAUUGGAACAGAUGUUGUAGUAUAUUAUAAAGGCAGACAAUGUAAGUUGAUCAUUAGGAAGAACUAAUCCUUCAAGAAACUUGGAGUAAAACUGCCCAAGAGGGAUGCUCUGUAUCAGAUGCUAACAUCAACACAAUCCAUUCUUCUUGUUAAGGAUGAAGUCAUAUGUACACAGAAGUGAGUCACCACAGCACGAUAAGCAAUUGCACGAUAAGCAAUUGCUCCAUUUCUCCAUGUAACUUGCUCACAUGCCUAUCUUGGAAGUGCUGAAUAUUCUCUUUGGGUCUGACCUAUGAAUGUCAACAAAUCUCUACUUUCUCCACAUGUCACUUGACUACUGUUUAGCCUUUUAUUCUUCAACAACAGUAACUAAUCUUUAAAAACAUUUACCAUAUAAUAACAAAAAUAGUACUGAAGAGUUCCAGUAUUUUAUGUUUACAUGUCUUAUUUUGUUUAAUCCUAAUAAACUAAUCUAUAAGGUGCUUAUUGUUGUCUCCUUUUUACAGAUAAGGAAACUGAGGUCUACAGAGGAAAAAAUAACAGCUUCGGUGUCACAUAGGUUGUAAGCAGAGGAACUGGGCUACAAAUCCGGAUCUGUCUGGCUCCAAGGCCAGACUUCUACACUUCUAUACAGCAGUGGUUCUCAAAGUGUGGUCCCCACACCAGCAGCAUCAGCAUCACCUAGGAACUUGUUAGAAAUGCAAAUACAGUCCCACCCAAGCAUACUGAAUCAAAAACUUUGAGGCUAGGGCCCAGGAAUCUGUUUUAACAAAUCCUCCUCACUAAGAUUCUGAUCCCUGCUCAAGUUUGAGAACAACUGCUGUAUAUCACACUACCUUUACAUAAUAAUAUUAAGGGAAGUAAAUAAGUCUGUGAGCAGAAAUUAUCUGAAAGACUUCCUAAAGAAGGUAUACUGUAAGCCAAGCCUUAGAGGAUAGAGAGAAUAUAAGUUGGUAUAAACAGUGGCACUGUUUCUAGCAUUUAUUCCUAUCUUCUUUAUGGUACUAUGAACUUUGAAGGAAGUAUAAUACAAUGCUCAGUUCAGUACUGAUACAUAUAUAUACUCAAGGCAUUUUGUUCAAUGAAUAAAAUUUUUGAUAAAGGGUACCUAAAUAUACCAAAUAUAAUCUUGUUUCAGGCCUUAAGUGAAAUUGAUUUUUACACUUCUGGAUAAUCUAUGUACAGCCAAUUAUAUUUCAAUGUUCUUAUCUUUAAAGUCUAUCUCGAACUCUUAAACCCCUCAGCACAAAGUGUUCAGGCCCUUAUCUUAUAUGGCUCUCAGCAUGAGUGCCACGUGCUUCUGUAACACUGUGAAGAUAACACGGACAAUUAUGGUCAAUUAGCUUUAACAAGUAGAUUAUUGCCUGAACAGUUGAAAGAAGACACAUCAAAUUUAGUCUUGUUAAAUUGAGAAUUUUUAAGAAUGGGAGAAAAAAAUUAAAUCCUAUGAAAAAGAAAAAUAAUACAUUUUGUAGAAUAUGAGAUAUACUUCAUUCAUUAAAAUCUGAAGUGGGCCCCAUAUCUAAUAUAUAGAAGAUUAUAAUUGGUAUUUCCAUUCUAAUUCAUACAAUGCUAAAAUGUUAAGAUUGUGAAUUCUCUUCUAUUAGAGAUAGUUCCAUUGGUACAGAUCACAUAAUAAAAAUAAUAUAUAUUUAUUUUUCAUAGUAGCAAAGCCCUUGCCAUAAUUUUGAUGAGCACUCUUUAGAUAUGCAUUAGCACAUAAAUGCUUAUAUAAUUUUGAAUUCAUAGAGUGCUCCCUAAAAGAAUCUUAUGUCCUAAAAACUUAUACCCAAAAUGGCCUGAAUGAUAAAAGACUUUUCACUGUGAGAAAUGUGCUCCUCCCCCAAAAGCAAUUGGGAAAUGAGAAGCAACAAGCAAACAAGAGGCAGAUAAGGCAUGUCUUAAUCAAAUAUAUAUAUGGAGUCUUAAAUAUUCUUGCAUACUUUUACAUUCUUACAUAUACAGAAAGAUUUCUUUAGGAAGAUGGCUAUUUUUGUUAAUAUAUAUAUAUGUGUGUAUCAUAACUUCCUCCAGGACACUUUAAAAUACGGAUCUAAUUUGACGGAAUCUAGACUGCCGGAAAAGAAGUAGUUCACAGCUAAGAUAAAUAAAAUUUAAAGGACAGAGAUCAAUGUCUAUGGAAUUCAAAAUGCUUUGAGCCAACAUGUAAAAGCUAUAUUAUAGCCUAUUGCUUAGGACAGAGAAGUCAUACUUACAGCAAAUAAAAGCCUGAUCCAGGCAGUUAAGGUUUAUAAUCUCCCUCCCUUCAGUGUGGGCUGGACUUAGUGACUUGCUUCUUACAAAUAGAAUAUGGCAAAAGUGAUGGCAUAUCACUUCUGAGAUUUGUUUUCAUAAGUUGUGGCUUUCAUCUUAGAUGCUGUCUCUCACUCCCUCGCAUACUUGCUCUGAGAGAAGUCAGCUUGCUAUGUUCAGGGCCCACAUAGCAAGGAACUGAGGGAGGCCAACAGCCAAUAAAGAACAGACACAUAAGGCCAACAUUCCAAGAGGAAGUGAAUCCUGCCAACAACCACAGAAGGGAGCUUGGUAAUGCAUCUUUCCCCAGCCAAACCUCAGAUGAGAUUGCAGCCCUAUCCAACAGCUUAGCAAUAGCCUCACAAAAGACCCAUAGUCAAGACUCAUAGAAAAUAUGAGAUAAUGAAUAUUUCUUAUUUUAAAUCAUUAAGUUUUAGGGAUAAUUUGUUAAGCAGUGGUAGAAAACUAAAACAAAGGAUGAUUUGGAGUCCUGAAGAGAAGCUAAAAUAGAACUCACAACUAUAGCUCAGCAUUGACUCAAACUUGAAAAGGGGAAUGUAUUUUUGAUGUGUGUAAUGCAAAGGUCAAUCCCUAGGUAAGAGAAAAGAUCUUGAGACUCAGGUAGUAAUGACAGCAGAAGAGAUUGGAAAGAUGAAUCCAGGUUCUAUAUCCUUCUCAAGUAACCCAGUAAAAUGAGAAUUUACUUUUAAUUUUCCUUAAAAUAUAUGCCUCAAAAUUCCUUUGUGAAAUAUAAACAUUUGGUUGUACAUUAGAAUUAACUCUUCUGGACUAUGUUAAAGAAAAAGGUAGGAAAAUGGGGAACUGAUAUGGUUAGGUUGUGUCCCCACCCAAAUCUCAUCUUAAAUUGUAACUCCCACAAUUCUUACAUGUCAUAGGAGGGACCUGGUAGGAGGUAAUUGAAUCAUGGGGGUAGGUCUUUCCCAUGCUGUUCUCCUGAUAGUGAAUAAGUCUCAUGAGAUCUGAUGGUUUUAAAAAGGUGAAUUUCCCUGCACAAGGUCUCUCUCUCUUUAUCUGCCGCCAUCCAUGUAAGAUGUGACUAGCUCCUCCUUGCCUUCCACCAUGAUUGUAAGGCCUCCCUAGCCAUGUGGAACUGUAAGUCCAUUAAACUUCUUUUUCUUCACAGUCUCGGGUAUGUCUUUAUUAGCAGCAUGAAAAUAGACUAAUACAGUAAAUUGGUACCAGUAGAGUGGAGCACUGCUGAAAAGAUACCUGAAAAUGUGGAAGCGACUUUGGAACUGUAUAACAGGCAGAGGUUGGAACAGUUUGGAAGGCUCAGAAGAAGGCAGGAAAAUGUGGAAAAGUUUGGAACUCCCUAGAGACUUCUUGAGUAGCUUUGACAAAAGUGCCGAUAGUGAUAUAAACAAUAAGACUGAGGUGGUCUCAGAUGGAGAUGAGGAACUUAUUGGGAACUGGAACAAAAGUGACUCUUGUUAUGUUUUAGCAAAGAGACUGGAAGCAUUUUGUCCCUGCCCUAGAGAUUUGUGGAACUUUGAACUUGAGAGAGAUGGUUUAGGGUAUCUGGUGGAAGAAAUUUCUAAGCAGCAAAGCAGUCAAGAGGUGAUUUUAAAGCCAUUCGGUUUUAUAAGGGAAGGAAAGCAUACAAGUUCAGAAAAUUGGCAGCCUGACAAUGAGAUAGAAAAGAAAAUCCUGUUUUCUGAGGAGAAAUACAAGCCGGCUGCAGAAAUUUGCAUAAGUAAUGAGGAGCCAAAUGUUAAUGGGGGAAAUGUCUCCAGGACAUGUCAGAGGUCUUCACAGCAGCCUUUCCCAUCACAGGCCUUGAGGCAUAGGAGGAAAAAGUGGUUUCAUGGGCAGGUCCUAGGGUCCCCAUGCUGUGCGGCGCCUAGGGAGUUGGUCCCCUGUGUCCCAGCCACUCCAGCCAUGGCUGAAAGAGGCCAAUGUAGAGCUUGGGCCAUGGCUUCAGAGGGUGCAGUCCCCAAGCUUUGGCAGCUUCCACAUGGUAUUGAGCCUGCGAGUGCACAGAAGUCAAGAAUUGAGGUUUGGGAACCUCCGCCUAGAUUUCAGAGGAUGUAUGGAAAUGCCUGCGUGCCCAGGCAGAAGUUUGCUGCAGAGGUGGGGCCUUCAUGGAGAACCUCUGCCAGGUCAGUGCAGAAGGGAAAUGUGGGUCAGAGCCCCCACACAGAGUCCCUACUGGGGCGCGGCCUAGUGGAGCUGUGAGAAGAGGGCCACCAUCCUCCAGACCCCAGAACGGUAGAUCCACUGACAGCUUGCACUGUUCACCUGGAAAGGUCACAGACACUCAACUCCAGCCCAUGAAAGCAGCCAGGAGUGAGGCCAUGCCAUGAAAAGCCACAGGGAUGGAGUUGCCCAAAACAGUGGGAACCCACCUCUUGCAUCUGUGUGACCCAGAAGUAAUACAUGGAGUCAAAGGAAAUCAUUUUGAAGCUUUAAGAUUUGAGUGCCCUGCUGGAUUUUGGACUUGCAUGGGGCCUGUAACCACUUUGUUUUGGCCAAUUAGUCUCCCGUUUGGAAUAGCUGCAUUUACCCAGUGCCUGUACCCAAUUGUAUCUAGGAAGUAACUAACUUGCUUUUGAUUUUACAGGCUUAUAGGCAGAAGGGACUUGCCUUGUGUCAGAUGAGACUUUGGACUGUGCACUUUUGAGUUAAUGCUGAAGUGAGUUAAGACUUUGGAGGACUGUUGGGAAGACAUGAUUUGUUUUUUAAAUGUGAGGACAUGAAAUUUGGGAGGGGCCAGGGUGGAAUGAUAUGGUUUGGCUAUGUCCCCACUCAAAUCUCAUCCUGAAUUGUAACUCCCACAAUUCCCACGUGUUGUGAGAGGGACCCAGUGGUAAGUAAUUUAAUCACUGGGGCAGGUCUUUCCUGUCCUGUUCUCAUGAUAGUGAGUAAGUCUCACAAGAUCUGAUGGUUUUAAAAAGGGGAGUUUCUCUGCACAAGCUCUCUCUCUGUUUGCCAGCUGCCAUCCAUGUAAGACAUGACUUGUUCCUCCUUGCCUUCCACCAUGAUUUUGAGGUCUCCCCAGCCACGUGGAACUGUAAGUCCAUUAAACCUCUUUUUCUUCCCAGGCUUGGGUAUGUGUUUAUCAGCAGUGUGAAAACAGACUAAUACAGGAACUAUAAGAGGAAGAAAAAAAGACUAGAGAGACAUUUGACCCUACAAGGUUAGCCUUUGAGAGAGAAAGUUUCCUACUUGGGCUUUCUUAAAAAAAAAAAAAAAAAAAAAAAAAAAAAAGACUCACUAUAGCACUUAUUUUGUAGUACAAUUAUUGGUUUAUCUAUCAUAUGUACCAGACAAAGAGAAACUUGGAUAGAAAUUGGGCCUUAUUUAGAUAUGUAUUCUAACACAUUUUUCAGGGUAGAACAAAGUAAGCAUUUAUGUAUUUAGUGAAUAGCAUUUAUGUAUUUAGUGAAUAAAUAUAUCAGUGAGUAACUCUAAUGGUUAGGGUUCCUUAUUAUGGUGUCAUAUUGAAAGUAUCAGAUUACACAGAAUGAGAUAUCUCAAUUUAAGAGAUAACUUAAGAAGUUCUUGGUUCCAUUUAAGAUGGUGUUAAGCCUGCUACACCCUAACUCUCCUAUCGUACAUCAUUGAGUUUACCAGCUUAGACAUCAGGGCAGCCCAAAUCCUAGAACUGUGCAGCAAGUGUGGGCAGGAAAAUCUCCAAAAGAAGUAUUAUUUUUAUUAUAUCAGAAGACUGGGUAGAAGCAUGCCUGAGAGUGUGGAAGAAAUCUCUGGGUUUUGGUUUAUUUAUUUAUUUAUUGUUUUCUCUAUUCCAGCCCUACCCCAAAGUAAGCCCCCAUGUGAGGGCAGUGACAAUGGUGGUUAUACAGAUGCCAAAAAACCACAGAAAAAGCACUUAUCUAUAGCCAGAAGACCCAGGAAAGAGCCCUCUGACCACCCCUGAAGGGCGUGGCAAAAAGUCAGGUUAUUCCUCUUUCCUCUUGCCACUGUGUGGCAAAUAAAGACUCAGUUAUAGGAAAGGCACAACAGUGUGAGAAGGCUAAAACUCAGAGAGAAACUGCAGCUUUCUAGCCAGAGAACUGGGAUAAGAGAUGCCUGGAAGCUGGGGAAAUCACAGAAGAGGUGAAGUGCUGAAGGAAUCACAGAAGAGGUGAAGAGCUGAAGAAGAAGAUUCUGUAAAUUUGUGUACCUCUGUAUGAACUGACAGAAGUCUUAGGCUCACCCACAAGAUGAACAUGCUCAAGACAGGCCAAAAAGAGCAACAUGAAGGCUUUAGAACUGACCUAGAGUGUAGACUCCACAGAGGUCCCAGACUGGCACCCAGCGGCACACACAUGGGAUAGAUACAAACAGCUGUAAAGUCUUUAAAAACUGAACCACUGCCUACAGAAGGUAGUCAGAACAUGUAGUCUAAACGUCUCUGGGUUGAUUAUCUACUAAAGCAACCAGAACAACAAAACCAACAAUUUCCAGGAGAUUUUUACAUGACCACAAGGCUCAUAACAUAACACUCAAAAUUUUCGUGAUAAAAUCCAAAGUUACUUGGCAUAUAAAGAACCAAGUAAAUCUAAAUGGAUCAUAAGAAAAAAGCAAUCAUGAAAUGCCAAUUCCAAGAUGCCAGAGGUUGGAAUGAUCGGACAAAUAUUUUAAUUCAGUUAUUAUAAUCAUCUUCAAGUAUAGUCAUCUUUUGCUAAUGUGAUUGUUGUAAUAAACUGUCUUUCAUCUUUGA